GUUGCCUAAACCUCUGCCACCCACCUGUGAACUUCACUUUGCCACAGGGAGGCACUGAACUGAAAAACUGCCUUGUAAGAGGUGUCGCCCCUCUGUCUACUCCCUUUCUUAUAUCAAGAGGGGAAAAACACGUAACUACCUCUACCCGAUCUGGUCACCAUACGCCUAUUACCUUUACUGUUACAAGUACCGGAUCACUCUCCGGGAGAAGAUGCUGCCUCGUUGUUAUAAAAGCAUCACUUAUAAGGAAGAGGAGGACUUGACACUCCAGCCCCGUUCCUGCCUCCAGUGCUCCUGAGUCCCUAGUAGGCCUCCAGGAGGGCAAAAGCACCGAGCAGGGUAACCACGACCAGCUUAAAGAACUGUAUUCGGCUGGGAACUUGACGGUGCUGGCUACUGACCCCCUGCUCCACCAGGACCCAGUACAGUUAGACUUUCACUUCCGCCUUACCUCCCAGACCUCUGCCCAUUGGCACGGCCUUCUCUGUGACCGUCGACUCUUCCUGGAUAUCCCAUAUCAGGCCUUGGAUCAAGGCAACCGGGAAAGUUUGACUGCAACCCUGGAGUACGUGGAAGAGAAGACAAAUGUGGACUCUGUGUUUGUGAACUUCCAGAAUGAUCGGAACGACAGAGGUGCCCUGCUGCGGGCCUUCAGCUACAUGGGCUUUGAGGUGGUCAGACCAGAUCACCCUGCCCUCCCUCCCUUGGACAAUGUCAUCUUUAUGGUGUAUCCCCUUGAAAGGGAUGUUGGCCACCUGCCCAGUGAGCCUCCUUGAACAUGCUUAUUCCAACGCUUUGAGGGGCUGGAAGCCUUGACACAUGGAAUCAGGGGCCCGGGAUGUGAUUCAGGACACUUUCCAUCCUAGGAAUAAAGGGUAGUGCAAUCA